AUGACUGGGCUCAUUGCCCACCAAGCCCUGUAUGUGCACACGGACCUGAUGCCCCUGGCCCCAGCGCCGCUGGCCCUCGACGUGAACACGCUCCUCAGUGAGCAUUCUUGGGCAGUGCACAACCUCCCCAGCCAUGCCAGCCCGCGCUCAGGCCUCCCCCGUCUUCCCCGUCUCUCCGGCGUCGGUUCUCAAGCUCGUCCUUCCCCGCCUCAUUUCUCCAAAAGUCCGCAGCAAAUCCUGGCAACUCCGCCUUCAGCAUCUACCGGGAGCCGGCACUUCCCACACCUGCGCAGACCCACCCGGGCCCCAGCCCAGGCAGCCCCUGCACGGGGAGCCCGCGGGUCUCUGGCGCCCGCUCGGGACGCCUCCCCAGCGCUCCCCGCAGAGCGGCCAGGGGGUCUCGCGAGUCCGCGCCAGCUCGGGAUCCCCGGAGCCUCCCCUGGUGCGCUGCAGCCACGCAGGCCUGCGUCCCGAGGCCCACACGGCUUCUGCGCGGCAUCCUCAGGACGACCUGGAGCCAAAUCCACACGGGACGGCACAGCAGCGUCCUGCCGAGCCCGCCUCGUCCGCCAGCGCGCACGAUUCACCGCGCCUGCUGCGGGACGGGCGGACGCGGGGCUGGGCUGGAAUAGCCGGCUCACGGAGGGCUCCGGCAGUGUUUGUUCAGAGGAGCGCGGCGCUGGUAGCAGGCGACGCCAGGACUCUUCUCCCCAGUGGUUCCAGUCAGCGAGCAGGACAGAGGAGCCCGGAAGAGGCGCCGUGCACUUCCGGGUCGAAGAGCGCACGGCGGCGGCAGAGGCGGCGGCGGCCGGGCCUAGGAGCGACUCUCGGUCGUGCAGCGGCGGCGAGCGCUCGCGAGCGGCUGCGGGACGCGAGGUUUCCGGGUAA